GAAAGGCAGGGAGGGGAGGUUGUCCCCUGCUGAGAACCAUUGGUUUAAGGUUAAUCUGGCUCUGCUUUCAUAGACUACUCUGUUACCCAGGCUGGAGUGCGGUGAUGAGUGAUCAUAGCUCACUGCAGCCUUAAACUCUAGUGAUCCUCCCGCCUUGGCCUUCCAAAGUGCUGAGAUUACAGAUGUGAACCACCACACCCAGCCCAGUCAAUUUGUUUUUAGAAUGUUCCCAAGAAUAUAGUUAUGUUGCUAAAUAAGAUACUAAAAUAAUCCCAUACUAUAUUUCUUGACAGAAAAACUAUUAAAAUGUAUACAUGAUAAAAAUUUCUUUUAUGAAGCAAAAUAUGUUUUGUUUUGCUCAUGAACGUGAGGUAUUUUGGAAAAAUGGUAAAGAAGUGCAGAGUCAAGUCAUAGCGACUAAUAAUGGGUUAUUUUCUUAAAUUGUAUGCUUAUGUUAAUUCUCACAGUCUUUUUGUUUGGGUCUGUGACAGAUCUUACAAAAGAUCUUUUAGACCUAUGAUUCUUAACAAAAUUAAAGAAUUAAGUCGGAACCAAUUUUCCACAAUGUCUCAUCUAAGAAAGGACUCACAGCCCAGCAGCCCAGGAGAUGACGCAAUGGACAGGAGUGGGCUCCCUGACCUUCAAGGAAGAUUUGAGCUAUCUGGGAAAAACAGACAGUAUCCACUGGAUGCAUUGGAACCCCAACCCAGCAUUGGGGAUAUUAAGGACAUUAAAAAAGCAGCCAAGUCUAUGCUAGACCCAGCACAUAAAUCUCAUUUCCACCCUGUGACCCCAAGUUUAGUAUUCUUGUGUUUCAUAUUUGAUGGGUUACACCAGGCAUUACUGAGUGUUGGUGUGAGCAAGAGGUCUAAUACUGUGGUUGGGAAUGAGAACGAGGAAAGGGGUACUCCUUAUGCUAGCAGAUUCAAAGAUAUGCCUAACUUUAUUGCCCUUGAGAAGUCAUCAGUUCUCCGCCACUGCUGUGACCUUUUGAUAGGCAUUGCGGCUGGAUCAAGUGAUAAGAUUUGCACCAGCAGUCUCCAAGUUCAGAGACGAUUCAAGGCAAUGAUGGCAUCUAUUGGAAGACUUUCACAUGGUGAGAGUGCUGAUCUGCUAAUCAGCUGCAAUGCAGAAUCAGCCAUAGGUUGGAUCAGCUCAAGACCAUGGGUUGGAGAAUUAAUGUUCACACUUCUAUUUGGAGACUUUGAAUCCCCUCUACACAAGCUACGCAAGUCAAGUUAGUUGCCAAGAAAGCACAGAUGACAACCUAUUAAUGCUGUGAGAAUGUUUCUAGAUCAGUGCAUGGAUGGCUCCAUUGCUCUACGGGCCAUUGUGUCUGAGAUCCCAGUCUUUGAGGAGAAAAAAAACAAUGGUUAAAAAGGCAUUGGGGAAAUAUUUUGAGUUUGGGGGUGUACUUUGCCACCCCAUUAUUGGGGAGCUGUCACCACGAAUGUUCCCAAACUUAGCAACAGCGGCAAACUACUGGGCCAAGAUGAGCAACCCCACAUUUUUGGGAUUUAAAGCUCCUGAUGUUAUACCAGGAUCAACCAUCACACUCCCUUUGCUUCAAAUGGCAUCUACCCCGUAAGAUCUUGAGGGGGGAGUGUUGGGUGGAAUCAUAGAUCCAUGCACUCCUAACAUGAACUAAUUCUCAUUAUUUAAAAAAAAAAAAAAAAAAA